GUGGACGGUACGCGGAGGCGCGAGGAGGGAGGCGCCUGGCGUUGCCGCGGCGCUGGGAAACUGUCUUUGCAGCGGCGACUGGGCGCCCAGCGGCGUGUACUGGGAUUUCUGUGAGCAGAGGCUGCCGAGAGGGGGCGCUUGGAGGGCCACCGGCGGCUUCGAAAGCUUCGCAGCCGGAAGCCGCCGGUUGGCGGCCUGGAUUUACCUUACGAAAGGUUUUAACCAAGGACUUGAGGUUUCUCAGGUUUUAAAUUUAAACUAAUAUGCUGUGUCCUUUAAUCGGAAAAGGCUCUGACCUUAUUUUUUCCCGUUAAGAAACAAGCGAUUACUUCAUUGGAGGGAAAAUGAAUCGUUCCUCAAAUGUACCACGUAAAGGUAUUCUGAAAUCAGGUACAAGAUCCUUACAAAAAGUUCGCAGAGUACAUUUCGCAAAUGCACGAAAUGCAAGAUCAUUACUAUCAAUGCUUAAAGACAUUUCAGCUCAAAUAAUACAGAGGGCUUGGUUAUCUCAUACAAACAAAAUGAUAUUUCGACUCCUAAAACACGCAAUUUGUGCAGCGGAAUUCUAUGUAACACAUGAAAUACUGAAGAAAGUGGCCCCCUUAGAGGCUAAGCUUAUUAAGGAUCCUACUAUGCAGUGUAAAAUUAGAUUCAGAUUUAGAGGUGAAACGUUUCCACCUUUCAUCGUGUUUAAAAUUUUUCUUCAUACUGAUGGCCAUGGUUACAAGUAUUUUAGUGGAAAAAAUGUAUUAAUGCCGUCAAGUAAGGCAGUGGAUGAUGCUUGCAAACUAAUGGGGGAAAGGAAAUUUCACCGUAUAAUUAUGGAAGAUGAACGUAUUUUCCCGAAGUCCAAAGUAACUGAUAUAAUGGAUGUUGUCACCAUGCAAGAUUAUGUACAAUAUCGCAGUUUUUUCGAUGAGGCCCCUGCAUUUUCUGGCGGCAGAAAUAACAGCUGGCGCAAAUUAAAUCUUGAAAAUAUUCCCAGGACAAUGCUAAUGUAUGACAUAGUUCAUUAUUCAGAGUCUGGAGUGAUCUCAAACCGUCUACGAAAUGAAAUGAAGUUUCUGUUACAGAGACCAGUAACGCAAGAGAUCCAUAAGCACCAGCUACGGAUUGUUUCUGAAAUUAGGGGUCCAUACUUAACUGUCCAACCUCUAUAUCGGCCCUACAAACAGCAAAAUCAAGUUAAAUUUCUGGGUCGUCGAUCCAAGCAAGCUCAAAUGAAAGUUGAAAAAAUGAGAAAAGUUUAUUUGGCUAAAGAAAAAAAUACUUCUGAGGUGACUGAACCAAAAACGGGCCCAUCAGGUACAAAGGAUAACUAUCAUCUCCACUCCAUCUUUUGACAUUGUGAAAACUAAGGAAUCUAUGUCAGAGUGUCAGCUGGAAAAAGAAAAAAGGACUCAUUUUCCUGGUAUCAAAACUUGGCAGCUGGUGAUUCUCCAUCAUGAUAAUGAACAGUUAAUUGACAGAAAACCAAAGUUGUUUAACAAUCUGCUUGUCUGUCUAUAAAUAAUGAGUAUGUGUAAUAAAGGAAAAUAACAUAGAAUAA